GCCCUGUUCCAAAAAGCAAAACAAGGGAAAGUUGAUACACUGGGGAAGACCAGAUUAUUGAUGAGAAGUUGUUUUCUGAGCUAAAAAGUGUUUCAACAUCCCACACUGCCUGAUUGGGUUUACCAUCUCAUUGGCCUAUUUUCCAUACUAUAGCAUAGUGGGAAAGGUGUCUUCCAUCUCCCUUCCUCAUAACCCCUUAAUGAAGAUUGUUUCCAGCUGCUGCCAGCUGGGGUGAUGCUUGACACACAAAUCAAGAGUUAGCGGUGGCUCUCAAAGUGUGAAAGUAUAGGAAUCACCCUGGGAGCUGCACGCUGGGUUCAGAUCCGAUGUUUUCAAGGCAGGGCCUGGGCAUGUGUAUUUUCAACAGUCUCUGCAGGUGACACUAACAUACCUCAAAAUUAACAAACCCCUGGCGGAGGUCAUGCAUUGUCUCUGUAUGGACUGAGCUCAGCAGGGAGUAGACCUAGCAGAAACCGCUCACUGUAAUUCACCAGAAACUCCAGUACUGAGCACCUAAUGGGGGCCAGGCUCUGUGUUACGCACUGAGGGUACAGAAGUGACGAAGUCGCAGCCUCCCUGUCCAAAGAGCAGACAGGCUAGUGGGGAGUAGAUCUCUGAGUAGUGGGGUGAGGCCUGAUGGAAGGGUCUAUGGCUCAGGUAAAAGGCCCUGGCCCCUGUAUCUUAUUAAAACAAUUACAUGUCAGUCCCAGAAUCGCCUCUCCUAGGGAAGGGCUUCUGGCUUGUAAGCUCAGAUGUAACAAAGAAGGACACAGUGAUCAUCUCCAGAACCCACUAGAGGCAAGAUAAGGCAAAAUGGGUUUCAGUUCUCUGUCGUCAGGUGACUUUUGCUUGCACAGGUGGUAAAGUGAAUUUUCUUAUUUUCUUUUUUAUGUUUUUCCUUGAGGUAUAUCACAGAAAAAUUCUCGAGUCUAAAGUGUACCCCUUGAGGGAUUUUUUUUUCAUAUGCAUACACCUGUGUAACUACUAUCCACAUCAAAGAGGGGGCAUUCUUGAGGUAGAAAAGACCUCACAGUGGGGACAAGUACCUGUUCAGCUUUGAACAGACUAAAGUAAAGCCUGAGAUCUCAGGGUACAGCUGCUCUCCUUGGCCACGCGUAAAAUUAACCCCUGAAAUUAACAAGUGUCUGGUGAGUAUCUGCAAUGUGUUGGAACCUUUCCAGGUAAGUUCCAGGGCCCCUCAACUCUUAAGUCCUAUAUGGGUGGUUUGCAGUUUUAGGAGUUGAAUUUCAAAAACAGAAUUUGUGUUGACCCUGUAUAAUCUCCAUCUGCUUUUCUUAAUUAGCAAUUGACCAACAUCACCUUCAAAGGGCUUUUGUAAACUUCUCAAAUUUCUCUCACUGUAAAUCUUGCCAAUAACUGAAUUCAUGAGGGAGUGAAUUUGGGGCCUUUACUUGGGAAGGGUACCUCCUUUCUGCCUGCCUCAAUUUGCCUUCCUUUUCCUUUAAUAUUGUAUUUUUAUUAUCUAGGGCAAAAAAAAAAGCAUACUAUUACAUUACAGCUUAUAAUGGCAACCCCUGAAGAAAACAGCAAUCCCCAUGACAGAGCAACACCCCAGCUGCCAGCACAGCUGCAGGAGCUUGAGCAUCGGGUGGCCCGGAGACGGCUGUCCCAGGCCCGCCACCGAGCCACCCUGGCAGCGCUCUUCAACAACCUCAGGAAGACAGUGUACUCUCAGUCUGAUCUCAUAGCCUCAAAGUGGCAGGUUCUGAAUAAGGCAAAGAGUCAUAUUCCAGAACUGGAGCAAACCCUGGAUAAUUUGCUGAAGCUGAAAGCAUCCUUCAACCUGGAAGAUGGGCAUGCAAGCAGCUUAGAGGAGGUCAAGAAAGAAUAUGCCAGCAUGUAUUCUGGAAAUGACAGCCUGCUUUCAAACAGUUUUCCUCAGAAUGGUUCCUCCCCUUGGUGCCCAACUGAGGCAGUCAGGAAGGAUGCUGAGGAGGAGGAAGAUGAGGAAGAGGAAGAUCAAGAAGAAGAGGAGGAGGAAGAAGAAGAGGAGGAGGAGGAAGAGGAGGAAGAGGAAGAGGAGGAGGAGGAAGAGGAGAAAAAAGUGAUCUUAUACUCCCCAGGAACUUUGUCGCCUGACCUCAUGGAAUUUGAACGGUAUCUCAACUUUUACAAACAGACGAUGGACCUUCUGACUGGCAGCGGGAUCAUUACCCCGCAGGAGGCGGCGCUGCCCAUCGUCUCCGCGGCCAUCUCCCACCUGUGGCAGAACCUCUCGGAGGAGAGGAAGGCCAGCCUCCGGCAGGCCUGGGCGCAGAAGCACCGCGGCCCUGCGACCCUGGCGGAGGCCUGCCGAGAGCCGGCCUGUGCCGAGGGCAGCGUGAAGGACAGCGGCGUGGACAGCCAGGGGGCCAGCUGCUCGCUGGUCUCCACGCCCGAGGAGAUCCUUUUUGAGGAUGCCUUUGAUGUGGCAAGCUUCCUGGACAAAAGUGAGGUUCCGAGUACAUCUAGCUCCAGUUCAGUGCUUGCCAGCUGCAACCCAGAAAACCCAGAGGAGAAGUUUCAGCUCUAUAUGCAGAUCAUCAACUUUUUUAAAGGCCUUAGCUGUGCAAACACUCAAGUAAAGCAGGAAGCAUCCUUUCCCGUUGAUGAAGAGAUGAUCAUGUUGCAGUGCACAGAGACCUUUGACGAUGAAGAUUUGUAAUGCAGAAGAGGAGCUGCGAGGGGAGGGACUGAAUGAGGUGGGCAGUUCCCAAGGUUGAAUGCUGGCAGCUAAGGUUGCACCUGCCUUGGCCUCCAGGACUCUUUGGAGUGGGUUGUUCCAGAAGCAUUUUGAUGAUUUUAGUUUCUGAUUAUUAUAAAGUAUAAGAGAAGC